AGUCUGGCGGCUGCAUUGCUGGGCGCGCCGCUCUCGUCUGAUCCCUGCUGGGGACGGUUGCCCGGGCAGGAUCCUUUACGAUCCCUUCUCGGUUUCUCCGUCGUCACAGGGAAUAAAUCUCGCUCGAAACUCACUGGACCGCUCCUAGAAAGGCGAAAAGAUAUUCAGGAGCCCUUCCAUUUUCCUUCCAGUAGGCACCGAACCCAGCAUUUUCGGCAACCGCUGCUGGCAGUUUUGCCAGGUGUUUGUUACCUUGAAAAAUGGCUACUGGACAGGAUCGAGUGGUUGCUCUCGUGGACAUGGACUGUUUUUUUGUUCAAGUGGAGCAGCGGCAAAAUCCUCAUUUGAGGAAUAAACCUUGUGCAGUUGUACAGUACAAAUCAUGGAAGGGUGGUGGAAUAAUUGCAGUGAGUUAUGAAGCUCGUGCAUUUGGAGUCACUAGAAGUAUGUGGGCAGAUGAUGCUAAGAAGUUAUGUCCAGAUCUUCUACUGGCACAAGUUCGUGAGUCCCGUGGGAAAGCUAACCUCACCAAGUACCGGGAAGCCAGUGUUGAAGUGAUGGAGAUAAUGUCUCGUUUUGCUGUGAUUGAACGUGCCAGCAUUGAUGAGGCUUACGUAGAUCUGACCAGUGCUGUACAAGAGAGACUACAAAAGCUACAAGGUCAGCCUAUCUCGGCAGACUUGUUGCCAAGCACUUACAUUGAAGGGUUGCCCCAAGGCCCUACAACGGCAGAAGAGACUGUUCAGAAAGAGGGGAUGCGAAAACAAGGCUUAUUUCAAUGGCUCGAUUCUCUUCAGAUUGAUAACCUCACCUCUCCAGACCUGCAGCUCACCGUGGGAGCAGUGAUUGUGGAGGAAAUGAGAGCAGCCAUAGAGAGGGAGACUGGUUUUCAGUGUUCAGCUGGAAUUUCACACAAUAAGGUCCUGGCAAAACUGGCCUGUGGACUAAACAAGCCCAACCGCCAAACCCUGGUUUCACAUGGGUCAGUCCCACAGCUCUUCAGCCAAAUGCCCAUUCGCAAAAUCCGUAGUCUUGGAGGAAAGCUAGGGGCCUCUGUCAUUGAGAUCCUAGGGAUAGAAUACAUGGGUGAACUGACCCAGUUCACUGAAUCCCAGCUCCAGAGUCAUUUUGGGGAGAAGAAUGGGUCUUGGCUAUAUGCCAUGUGCCGAGGGAUUGAACAUGAUCCAGUUAAACCCAGGCAACUACCCAAAACCAUUGGCUGUAGUAAGAACUUCCCAGGAAAAACAGCUCUUGCUACUCGGGAACAGGUACAAUGGUGGCUGUUGCAAUUAGCCCAGGAACUAGAGGAGAGACUGACUAAAGACCGAAAUGAUAAUGACAGGGUAGCCACCCAGCUGGUUGUGAGCAUUCGUGUACAAGGAGACAAACGCCUCAGCAGCCUGCGCCGCUGCUGUGCCCUUACCCGCUAUGAUGCUCACAAGAUGAGCCAUGAUGCAUUUACUGUCAUCAAGAACUGUAAUACUUCUGGAAUCCAGACAGAAUGGUCUCCUCCUCUCACAAUGCUUUUCCUCUGUGCUACAAAAUUUUCUGCCUCUGCCCCUUCAUCUUCUACAGACAUCACCAGCUUCUUGAGCAGUGACCCAAGUUCUCUGCCAAAGGUGCCAGUUACCAGCUCAGAAGCUAAGACCCAGGGAAGUGGCCCAGCGGUGACAGCCACUAAGAAAGCAACCACGUCUCUGGAAUCAUUCUUCCAAAAAGCUGCAGAAAGGCAGAAAGUUAAAGAAGCUUCGCUUUCAUCUCUUACUGCUCCCACUCAGGCUCCCAUGAGCAAUUCACCAUCCAAGCCCUCAUUACCUUUUCAAACCAGUCAAAGUACAGGAACUGAGCCCUUCUUUAAGCAGAAAAGUCUGCUUCUAAAGCAGAAACAGCUUAAUAAUUCUUCAGUUUCUUCCCCCCAACAAAACCCAUGGUCCAACUGUAAAGCAUUACCAAACUCUUUACCAACAGAGUAUCCAGGGUGUGUCCCUGUUUGUGAAGGGGUGUCGAAGCUAGAAGAAUCCUCUAAAGCAACUCCUGCAGAGAUGGAUUUGGCCCACAACAGCCAAAGCAUGCACGCCUCUUCAGCUUCCAAAUCUGUGCUGGAGGUGACUCAGAAAGCAACCCCAAAUCCAAGUCUUCUAGCUGCUGAGGACCAAGUGCCCUGUGAGAAGUGUGGCUCCCUGGUACCGGUAUGGGAUAUGCCAGAACACAUGGACUAUCAUUUUGCAUUGGAGUUGCAGAAAUCCUUUUUGCAGCCCCACUCUUCAAACCCCCAGGUUGUUUCUGCCGUAUCUCAUCAAGGCAAAAGAAAUCCCAAGAGCCCUUUGGCCUGCACUAAUAAACGCCCCAGGCCUGAGGGCAUGCAAACAUUGGAAUCAUUUUUUAAGCCAUUAACACAUUAGUGCUGCCCUCAGGCUUGCCUGUAGGAUUUAAUAUUUUUUAUCUUUACAGAUCUUUAUCUUUAAUAUUUUAUCUUUACAGAUUUCCCUGAGAAAGGGAAUUAUGAAAUUUUUAAUACAAAAAAUAAUCCAUUUAGGUGCUGAGUUACGGUCCCAUCUCUUCACAGGCAUGGAUUCUAAUCCCACUGCUGACAGAGAUGUAAAAAUUCAUCCUACCAGAGUUUUUAAUCUUUAGCAUUUAGGGAGGCAGUGUCAUAAAGUAAAAAGUGUGUGGGCCUUGGAGUCUAAGAGACGUGGUUGCAAACUUAGCUCUGGUUAUUGCAAUGAGGGCCUUGAACAAGUCAUUUUCUUCACAUUCUCAUCUGUAAAAUGGAGAUAAUACCUUACAGAUUAUUGCAGAUUAAUAACAAUGUAUUCAAAUUAUGUAACUCGGCCGGGUACAAUGGCUCACGCCUGUAAUCCUAACACUUUGGGAGGCCGAGGCAGACAGAUCACCUGAGGUCAGGAGUUUGAGACCAGCCUGGCCAACAUGGCAAAACCAUCUCUACUAAAAAUAGAAAAAUUAGCCAGGCACGUUCCAGGCACCUGUGAUCCCAGCUACUUAGAGGCUGAGGCAGAAGAAUUGCUUUAACCUUGGAGGCGGAGGUUGCAUUGAGCUGAGAUCAUGCUAGUGCGCUCCAGCCUGGGCAACAGAGCGAGACUUCAUCUCAGAAAAUAAAAAAUAGGGGCCAGGCACAGUGGCUCAUACCUGUAAUGCCAGCACUUUGGGAGGCCAAGGCGGGCAGAUCACGAGGUCAGGAGUUUCAGACCAAUAUGGUGAAACCCCAUCUCUACUAAAAUUACAAAAAAAAUUAUCCAGGCGUGGUGGUGCACGCCUGUAAUCCCAGCUACUCAGGAGGCUAAGGCAGGAGAAUCACUUGAACCCAGGAGGCAGAGGUUGGAGUGAGCUGAGAUCGCGCCACCGCACUCCAGCCUGGGCAACAGAGCGAGACUCCAUCUCAAACAAAAACAAGAACAAAAACAAACAUAAAGUUGGCACAGAAAAGGGACCAAGUUUAAAAAAGGGUUUUAAAUGUAAUGAGACUUGCAUAGUUAAAAAAAAAAAAGGGAUUAUUUUUAUUUUUAUUUUUUAUUUUUGAGACGGAGUCUCCCUCUGUCGUCAGGCUAGAAUGCAGUGGUGCGUUCUCAGCUCACCGCAACCUCCGUCUCCUGGGUUCAAGCAAUUCUCCUGCCUCAGCCUCCCAAGUAGCUGGGACUACAGGCACGUGCUACCACACUCAGCUAAUUUUUGUAUUUUUAAUAGAGAUGAGGUUUCACCAUGUUGGCCAGGAUGGUCUCGAUUGCUUGACCUCAUGAUCCGCCUGCCUCGACCUCCCAAAGUUGCUGGGAUUACAGAUGUUAGCCACCGAUCCUGGCCCCCCCAAAAAAAGGAUUUUAAGAAAAACUUCUCUUGGCCGGGCGCAGUGGCUCACGCCUGCAAUCCCAGCACUUUGGGAGGCCGAGGCGGGCGGAUCACAAGGUCAGGAGAUCGAGACCACGGUGAAACCCCGUCUCUACUAAAAAAUACAAAAAAAAAUUAGCCGGGUGCGGUGGCAGGCGCCUGUAGUCCCAGCUACUCGGGAGGCUGAGGCAGGAGAAUGGUGUGAACCCGGGAGGCGGAGCUUGCAGUGAGCCGAGAGCGCGCCACUGCACUCCAGCCUGGGUGACAGAGCGAGACUCCGUCUCAAAAAAAAAAAAAAAAGAAAAACUUCUCUUUAGGCUGGGUGCGGUUCCUCAUGCCUAUAAUCCCAGCAUUUAGGGAGGCUGAGGUGAGUGGAUUGCAGGAGCUCAGGAGUUCGAGACCAGCCUGGGCAAGGUGGCAAAACCCCGUCUCUACUAAAAAAAAUUAGCUGGGCUUGGUGGCAGGCGCCUGUAAUCCCAGGUACUCGGGAGACUGAGGCAGGAGAAUUGCUUGAACCUGGAAGGUGGAGGUUGCAGUGAGUUGAGAUCACACCAAUGCACUCCAGCCAGGGUGAGAGUGAGAGACUGUCUCAAAAAAAAAAAAAACAAAAGAAAAACUUCUCUCUAGCUCUGUGACGGGCAGUUCAGAUAAUACCUUCACCAGAUUUACCUGUUUUCAGCUGAAGAAUGUGAGAUGAAGCCUUGAAACCCUAAAAGUGAUAUGGUAACUAGGGCAGGUCUUUCUGUACAUAAAAGUGACUUAAUAAACAGUGAAUUUCAUACAGGUAAACCCUAUUAUACCCUCAGUUCUAACCAUUGGCCUAUCUCUUGCGUUUUGUUCUAAUGUAGAAUUAGAUUGCUACUUGACUAGUUCAGGAACUCUGUUUAGAUCUGAUAAGUCAUAAUCAAAUCUUGCCAGGCGUGGUGGUUUAUGCCUGUUAUCCCAGCACUUUGGGAGGCCAAGGCAGGUGGACCACGUGAAGUCAGGAGUUCAAGACAAGCAUGGCCAACAUGGCGAAACCCUGUAUCUACUAAAAAUACAAAAAUUAGCCGGGCAUGGUGGUGGGUGCGUGUAAUCCCAGCUAGUUGGGAGGCUGAGGCAGGAGAAUCACUUGAACCUGGGAGGCAGAGGUUGCAGUGAGCCGAGAUUUCCACUGCAUUCCAGCCUGGGCGAUAGAGUAACUCUGUCUCAAAAAAACCCACUAGAUCAUCUCUAGAACAUUGCUACUCCCAAGUAUGAUUUGAGGAACAGCAGCCUCAGUAUCACCAGGGAACUUAUUAGAAAUAGUCUCAGCCUCACCACUAUUCCCACUUAAUUGUAAUCUGAUAUUAACAAGAUUUCCCAAUGUGGGUCAGGUGUGGUGGCUCAUGCCUGUAAUCCCACACUUUGGGAGGCCAAGGUGGGCGGAUCACUUGAGGCUGGGAGUUUGAGACCAGGCUGGCCAACAUGGGGAAAACCCAUCUCUACAAAAAAUAACAAAAAUUAGGUGUGUGUGGUGACGCAUGCGUGUAAUCCCAGCUACUUAGGAGGCUGAGGCAGGAGAAUCACUUGAAUCUGGGAGGCAGAGGUUGUAGUGAGCUGAGAUUGUGCCACUGCACUCCAGUCUGGGCAACAGAGUGACACUGUUUAAAAAAAAAAAAAUUCCCAAUGUGGGCCGGGUGCAGUGGCUCAUGCCUGUAAUCCCAGCACUUUGGGAGGCUGAGGUGGGUGUAUCACGAGGUCAAGAGAUCAAGGCCAUCCUGGCCAACAUGGUGAAACCCCGUCUCUACUGAAAAUACAACUGGGCGUGGUGGUGCACGCCUGUAGUCCCAGCUACUUGGGAGGCUGAGGCAGAAGAAUUGCUUGACCUGGGAGGCGGAGCUUGCAGUGAGCCCAGAUCGUGCCACUGCACUGCACCCUGGCGACACAGCAAGACUGUCUCAAAAAAAAAAAAAUUCCCAAUGUGUAUCUUAAAGUUUGAGAAAUGCUGAUCUAAAAGAUACUAAUGACCAGGUGUGUAGAGGACAUUUUCUUAAGCCCUUAAGUACAAAUUUAAGAGGUAAGUGCUUCAGCCAUUAGGGUUACUGGCUUGUUCAUCUUUCCCACUGAGUGUAAAUAUUUAGCUUAGGGUUUAAAAUUUGUUAUGUAGCUUUUUGCACUUGUCCAUGUUUAUACUACUGUAUUAUUAUUAUUUUUUUUUGAGAUGGAGUCUCGCUGUGUAGCCAGGCUGGAGUGCAGUGGUGCAAUCUUGGCUCACUGCAACCUCCGUCUCUCGGGUUCAAGCAAUUCUCCUGCCUCAGCUUCCCGAAUAGCUGAGACUACAAGCGUGCACCACCAUGCCCAGCUAAUUUUUGUAUUUUUAGUAGAGACAGGUUUUCACCAUGUUGGCCAGGCUGGUCUCUAUCUAGACCUCGUGAUCCAUCCGCCUCGGCCUCCCAAAGUGCUGGGAUUAUAGGCAUGAGCCACCACGCCCAGCCUAUAGUACUGUAUUCUUAUUCUCCACUCUUGUGUGUGAAAAGUCAGCUCUUUUGGCUUUUCUGUUAUGGGGAAACUUGAAUUACACAGGGAACCCAACUGAAGAAAAUGAACUGAAGUAGGUGGCGCUGGGUGAAGUGGGCCCAGAGAAUGGUGUACACAUCCCUCCCAUACAUAUACCCAAACUUCUAUUUUUUUAUGUGACGGAGUUUCUCUCAUCGCCCCGGCUGGAAUGCAAUGGCACGAUCUCGGCUCACUGCAACCUCCGCCUCCCGGGUUCAAGCGAUUCUCCUGCAUCAGCCUCCUGAGUAGCUGGGAUUAUAGGCAUGCACCAUCACGCCUGGCUAAUUUUUGUAUUUUUAGUAGAGAUGGGGUUUCGCCACGUUGGCCAGGCUGGUCUUGAACUCUUGAUCUCAAGUGAUCCACCCGCCCUGGCCUCCCAAAGUGCUGGGAUUACAGGCCUGAGCCACCAGGCCAGCCCCAACUUCUACUUUUUAUUUUAUUUAUAAAUUGGGGGGGGGGUUCUAUAUUUAGUUUGAAGAGGUGGGGAAGAUUUGAAAACCACUAGAUUUACCAGGAAAUUUUUUUCUUCAAAAAUAUUUUCUGCUUUUAUGAUACUUGAAUAUCUAAUAAAAGACAAUAUUUAGCCAGUCACGGUGGCUGAUGCUUGUAAUCCUAACACUUUGGGAGGCUGAGGUGGGUGGACUACUGGAGCCCUGGAGUUCAAAACCGGCCUAAGCCACAUGGCAAAACAGUCUUUACAAAAAAUACAAAGAUGGUGGCUUAUGCCUGUAGUCGUACCUACUCAGGAGGCUGAGGUUGGGAGGAUCACCUGAAUCUGGGAGUUUGGGGCUGCAAUAAGCCAUGAUUGUGCCGCUGCACUCCAGCCUGGGUGACAGUCUGAGACCCUGUCUCAAAAAAAAAAAAAAAAAAAAAAAAAAAAAAGACUACAUUCACUGUAUACGUGGCCUUUUCCCCCUAACUAGCUAUGUAGCUUCUUAAAGGCAAAGAUUCUUCAUAGUGCUUUGCACAUGAUAGGUGCUGAUACUCAUUGGAUGAAUGUAUAUAGUGAAGAAUUUUAGAUCUGAUUACCACAAUUGGGAUCAUAAACAUGUAUAAACUCCUUGGGAGUCUGCCUUAUAUACUUUUUAUCCCCCUAAAUGUUCCAUUAAUGUUGCAGAGAGGCUCACUAGUUCCUGGAGAUGUCUUAUUAAGUACUGAAAUGUGAUUUUCCAAAAUUUUCUUUACAAUACAGGCAAAAGAUAAGUAAAUUGUGGACAAAGCUUUCAUCUCUAUCAGCAGCUAUAGAGAGGAAGUAAACAGCUUAGCCCCUAAUACAGGAGGAAGUUGUUCAACUACAGGCUUGUUAGUAGCAAGUUAAACCAGUUACAUUUUAUAAAACAGCCUGAGUGGUAGGGAAGCUAUCACUUUAAUACUCUAGAGGCAGAAUGCCACAUAGGACUUUGGGUCACAUAUUUCUUUUCCAGGGUCUCCUCAAAAUGCAGUUUCUAUUUACAGUUGACUUUGGCCCCUAUUUACCCAUAAAAUGUCAAAAUCAAGUAGUAUGAACAUGGAAACAGGAGCAGGGACUAAGGUUUGGUCAAGUGGCCCUCAUUGUUCCAAGAGUAAUUUAGGCUAUGUAAACUUGAAAAAUAUGGGACCAGAUUACCUUUUGUCUCUAAAUUCUACUCUUCUUUAAGUAGCUGGCACUGUAUCUCUGCCAGGGCACAGAAGUGGGCUCCUUACUAUUCUGACCACUAGCAAGUGGCCAACUCUUCAAAUACAGGGUAGCUACCUAUUUCACGUGAAAGGCCUCAGUAUUCUGCUCACUUGAACUACGGAAAAUAGGCCACAAUACUUGGUUACAAUACUGGAACUCUGAACCUAUGUGGAGGAGAGAAAAACAAUGGUGAACGAGAUACCAGCUGGGCUCUUUCCACAUUCAGGGCUCAGCAGUGUUGGGGUUUCACUUGUCUCUAAUCCUGAAGAGGUAUCUAGCCCUGGAAGGAAGCUGAGCCUGUAGCUAACGCAUAAGCACAGUGUAUUCAAUAAAACAUUUUUAUUCUGUACAAUA